GGGUUAGGGCCCAGCGGGCAGCACCAAGGAGUCGCCGCCCGCCUGGCGACGACGGGCGGCUUCCUCGACCCUCCCCGGCAUGAGUCCGCGCGGCGCCCAGAGGCGUCCCGGCGCCGCUCUGCCUGGGAGAGGCUCCCCUCAGCGUCGGGGCCCCGAGGUGUCUGAGCCGGACUCCGGCCGCGCCGGGAGGCCGCCUUGACCCCGCGCGGAGGGUCCGCCCCGUUGUUGUAUAAGCCACCCCGCGGGCCGGCGACGGAGCUGGCCGCGGCGGCCGCACCGGCUCGGGCUCUGCCAAGGGACCCGGCCUGCCCCAAUGCCGCCGGCGGGCGGUGCCCGGUCGACCCUGCACCUGACUGCGAGGCGCGGGAAAUGACCGGGUCUGUCAGCCUCCCAUCGCGGCUUCCGUCUACAGGUCAGGAUGGCUAACUGGUUGGCUCCCCACAUGGUGCCCUACGUCUAUAUCACACCUUAAAGAAGCUGAAGAGAAGAUGUUAAAAUGUGUGCCUUGCACAUACAAAAAAGAACCUGUUCGUAUAUCUAAUGGAAAUAAAAUAUGGACACUGAAGUUCUCUCAUAAUAUUUCAAAUAAGACUCCACUUGUCCUUCUCCAUGGUUUUGGAGGAGGUCUUGGGCUCUGGGCACUGAAUUUUGGAGAUCUUUGCACCAACAGACCUGUCUAUGCUUUUGACCUAUUGGGUUUUGGACGAAGUAGUAGACCCAGGUUUGACAGUGAUGCAGAAGAAGUGGAGAAUCAGUUUGUGGAAUCCAUUGAAGAGUGGAGAUGUGCCCUAGGAUUGGACAAAAUGAUCUUGCUUGGGCACAACCUAGGUGGAUUCUUGGCUGCUGCUUACUCGCUGAAGUACCCAUCAAGGGUUAAUCAUCUCAUUUUAGUGGAGCCUUGGGGUUUCCCUGAACGACCAGACCUUGCUGAUCAAGACAGACCAAUUCCAGUUUGGAUCAGAGCCUUGGGAGCAGCAUUGACUCCCUUUAACCCUUUAGCUGGCCUAAGGAUUGCAGGACCCUUUGGUUUAAGUCUAGUGCAGCGUUUAAGGCCUGAUUUCAAACGAAAGUAUUCUUCAAUGUUCGAAGACGAUACUGUGACAGAAUACAUCUACCACUGUAAUGUGCAGACUCCAAGUGGUGAGACAGCUUUCAAGAAUAUGACUAUUCCUUAUGGAUGGGCAAAAAGGCCAAUGCUCCAGCGAAUUGGUAAAAUGCACCCUGACAUUCCAGUUUCAGUGAUCUUUGGCGCCCGAUCCUGCAUAGAUGGCAAUUCUGGCACCAGCAUCCAGUCCUUACGACCACAUUCAUAUGUGAAGACAAUAGCUAUUCUUGGGGCAGGACAUUAUGUAUAUGCAGAUCAACCAGAAGAAUUCAACCAGAAAGUAAAGGAGAUCUGCGACACUGUGGACUGAACACACUGAAGCUCUGAUGGGAAAACCUGGUGACUGAUAUAGUUGUUCAGCAAUAAUUCAUAGUCUGUGAUGAAGAGUAGUGAAUACAACACACAACCAGGCAGCCUUCUUGACUAUACUUUGCACAUGUUUUCUUUAGGAAUUCACUCACACAUUUAAACCAGUUAGUGCCUUCUAGAAGAAUGGCUUUCCUUUCUCCUACACAAAAUUGAAAUAUACAAGUCUCUAAAUAUAAUACCUUUAAAUAAAAGGUUAUUUGUCCCUCUGAUGUACUGAAAAACUGUAAUUUUUCAGCUGAAAAUUUUUUAAUCUAACUUUGCUAGUUAUUUUUAUAUUGCAAUCUAUAUUACCAAUUUAGGAAGUGAUUUCUGAGUCUCUUACACUGUAAAGGUGCACUUUAUUUUCUUUGUCUUCCCCAUCAUGUAUUUAUUGUGUCUUGAUAACUGAUAUUAAUCUAAAUUCAAUGUGUUUUUAUGUAAAAAUUUGUCAGUUGUUUAGAAUAUUUCACUUUGUUUUUGAAACGGAGUGACAAGGCAGAUUUUUGGUUAGAGGACGGGAGUUGAUCACUAUCAUUACUUUUUCUAGUUUACCUGUUUUUUAUAUUUAAGGCUGCUAAGCCAUGUUCAGCAUUUUAAAUGUGGUCUAUCCUGACAUACAGUGUAUAACAACAUAACUCCUUGGAACCUCCUAUGUGUGGUAUAAUUCUACUCUUCCAAGGAACAUGACUUCAAUACUUUCAGUGAUUCAGGUACUGAAAAGCCUUACCUAAAAGGCUGUUCUUUGUUUCCCCCUUUCAUACUAUUCUUUUCCAUGACCCAGGAUGCAGCAAAUGAAACAGAUUUCUUCUCUUAAGGGGAUAUUAAGACUGUUACUUCCUAGUAAGCCAAGUAAUACCAUAUUUUUAUUAACAUCUAACUUUUGUAGAUGGGUGCUAAAAUUGCAUACAUUUUAACCACUAAAAUAGAAAAACAAGUGGUGCUAUUAUGUCUCAUGGCACCAGAAAUGAGCUAGCACUUGGGUUUGUUGUUGCUGUUGUUUAUUAAGAGUAUUGUGUUAAUUAAAUCAUUACAUACUUGAAGUUAUAUUACAAAAAUUCUAGAAGGUUGAUUGAACUAUUUUUUUAGGAACUACCAUCAAGUGUAGCAUUUUCUUGCAGUUUUAAAAUGAGGAAAACUUCUUUGAAACUGUGAAAUGCUCCAUGUGGUAACUGGCUGCUGAGAAAACCCUUCACCAAAAAAAUAAAUAAAAAUUGAAUAGGAUUGUCAUCAAGAAGGCAUCUUUCGCUAACGUUGCUUGUCUAGGAGAAAGGUAGCUAUGUAAAUAAAAACAGUGAACUAGAGCAAAUAGUGGUUUAAUGGUUUUGUUAUUGCAUUUUUAAAAUGGUUAAUUAGGGAAUUUGUAGUUGUUAGGAAAUGUAAGGUUGUGUCACUGUUGAUUAACUGCCAGAAAGACUGAAUGUUCUAUUUUCAACAUUUCUCCCCUAUAAAAGAAUAGACAAAUUAUACUGAAGCAUGAUAUAAACAUCUUCCCAAUGAACAAUUUGUCUCACUUGUCAGAUUAACUAGGUUAGUGCAGGAAGCAACAUGAGCGCCAAGAUGUGUUGUCUGAUUUCUCUACCUUAAGAACAAUAAUAGUCUUUUUAGUUAGUAUUUUGGAUGGCCAGGUUUCAAACCUGUAUGUGGUACAAAUAAUUUGGGUAAUAUUUUUGUAUUUUUGUUUUACACACUCUCUAAUCUCAAUUAUCCUUUGCUGGGAGAAUGACAGGUUUCACUUAUACAGGAAGGUUUUUGCACAGGAAAUUUGGUCCCAGCCCUUGGAAGGAAGAAGUUCCUUCGUUUACUUAGUGAAUGGAGUUUCUGGCCGCAGAUGUGCCAAGUGAUUGAAGAAAGAUAUACCCCAAUAUCAAGUGAUAAUUUAUUUUCCUACAGACUGAAUUUGCUUUAUUUGAAAGAUGUUGUAACUCUUUUUAAAGUUAGAUUUUACCCUGAGGUAUAGUAUAUGUAAUUUUGUGAAGAUUGAGCUGGAAGGGAAGUUCACAAUCCUCACAUUUAAAAAAAUAUAGUGGGUGCUAAAUGUUUUCUUAAAAAUCUAGUACAGCAUUUGAUCUUUGUUAUGCACAGCAUACUUUUAUUUUACAGAAUAAAUUUUCCUGUGAUAGUCACAACAAGACAGCUGUAUAGUUUCUUGAGUCUUUUGUAUGGACCAGUCUCUGUAUAAUAGUUAACUACAGGACUGUGGAUCCAGCAAAUGUUCAGUAAAUGCUGCUGUUGUUCUUAGGGAAGGCUACUCUGGGUGUUGUGGCCGCCAUACAUGGCUUUACCUGGGUCCAUGCAUUCCCUUAAGAUGACUUCUGUUUUCUUCUUUUUUCUUCUGAUUUUCCAAAAAAAAAAAAGCCUUGCCUAAGGUUGGUUUUAGAAUAUGAUUUGCAGAACACUUUUGAAAUGUCUUCAUUCAUAUAUGUAAUAUAUAUUUAUACUUAAAGGGCCAUACGCGAUUUCAAUAAAACAAGAAGUACUGGAAAGAAUAAACAAAAAUAGCCAGAAGAUGCCUAGAAAAGAACAAUGUGGAAGGAGGGAUAACCCUAUUAAAUAUUAUAACAUAAUGUUUACAAUAUGAGAAAGUCUAGGAAUUUAGUACAUGAUAAAGCAUCUCAUUCAGAGAAAAAGGCUUUAAAAAUGGUGUUGAGAGAAGUGUGGUUAACCAUUUGGAAAAAAAAAUAAAAUUGAAUCGAUUUCUCACAGGAUACACAGGAUAAAAUCUGAAUAGAACAAAGACCCAAUUUUUAAAAUGAAACCCUCUUUCUAACUAGAAGAAAACAUAGAUGAAUUAUUGUAUAAUCUGACAGUGAGAAAAACUUUCCUAGGACUGAAAAUUCAGAAGCAAUAAAAAGAGAAGUCUAUAGAAGAAUUUUCAGCCAGAUGGAAUGGCUCAUGGCUGUAAUCCCAGCAUUUUGGGAGGCUGAGGCAGAAGGACUGCUUGAGACCAGGAAUUCAAAACCAACCUGGGCAACCUAGUAGGACUGGCUCUACCAAAAAAAAAAAAAAAAAAAAAUUAAGUACCUGGCCUGGGUUCCACCUACUUGGGAGGCUGAGGUAGGAGGACUGUGAGCCCAGGAGUUUGAGGAUGCAGUAAGCCACUGCACUCCAGCCUGGGUGACAGAGAAGAAAAAAGAUUUUUUUGGAUAGCUGAAAAUAUUUGCAGCAUUUAUCACAGAGGGCUAAUUGUAGCCCUAUAUAUGAAGAAUUUUAAACUAUGAGAAGAACCCGAAGAAUAGGCAAAAGGAUGUGAACAGACAGUUAACAGAAAAUAGAAUGCAAAUGGUCUUUAAACAUACAAGGAUAUGCAUAAAAAGACAAAUGCAAAAUAAAAUAAAAUAAUGGAAAUACCUUUCUUACCUGUGAGAUUGGGGAAAAUCCAAGUUAGGCAAUGCACUCUGUUGAGACAAUAGGGAAACAGGCACUCCAAAAAUUACAAAUCCCUGUGGAUGGUAUUUGUUAACUAGCAAAGUUAAAUGAGUAUAUCCUUCAACCUGGCAGACCCAGUUCUAAGAAUCCAUAUGAGAUGCACUUGCAAGAAUAUGAAAUAGUAUAUGCACAAAGAUCUUGAUUACAGCACUGUUUCUAAUAGCUACAGACUGGAAGCCAGCCAAAUCUCCAUUGAUAGGGAAUUGAUGGAAGGAACUAGGGUAUAUCUAUACAAUGGGAUACUACACAGCUGUAGAAAGGACUGCGAACUAUUUUUGUAGUUCUGGUCUGGAGAAAUCUCCAGAAUAUAGGAAAUGAAAAAUGUAAAGCACAGAAGAGAAUGUAUGGUGUGCUGUCUGUUGUAUAACGAAGAGACAAAUGGAAAAAAUAUGUAUUUGCUUUUUUUGUAAAGCAAUAGAAGAAUUAGUUAUACCAAUAACUAAUAAAAUGAUCUCCUUGUUAGUGGUGGUAGGGAGCUAGACAAGGAUGGCAACUAUUUCUGUAUCUUACAUACCUUUUAUUUUGAGGCCCUGUCAAUGUUUUAUAUAAUAAACAUUUUUUGAAAAGGCAACUCUUAAAACUAAAACAAACUUAACAGUCUGUCAAGUUGGUGAUAUAACCCCACAGAAGACUUACUUCAAGUGACUUGAAAACUUAGUAUUUUGUCUGUACUUUGCUAAUGGAAUAUAUCCUACAGACCAAACAACCACAAAUAAAUCUUAAACUGCA